GUAGUUCCGGGCGGAAUGAGAGCAGCACGCCUGGCUCCGCUCCUUCUUACUCAUGCGCGACUCCGAGCUGGCCAAAGAAGUUCGUCCCCUUUGUGAGGCCCGGGAUGGGAGGCGCCCGGUUCCCCCAGGGACAGCUUCAAGCGGUAGGGACAGACAUCUGAGGACCCAGCCUCAGGGAUGCUGUCCCCGGGCUUCCAGGCUCCAGCGCCGUAGGACUGAGGCAGACUCCACGGUGAGAAAGAGACCCGAUCUAACCCAGGCCUUUCAUCAGAGCCCAGGAGGGAAGGCAGGAAGUGGGACCACGAGGCCCGGGGGGCUUCUAACUCGUCUGGCCAGGGAGAUCUGAAUUGGGGUGAAGAGCAGAAUCUCCAGAACAAGGAGGAGGUGGUGAUCAUGGAGACAGAUUUGGCUGAAAUGCCUGAGAAAGGAGUUCUGUCUUCCCAGGAUUCUCCCCAUUUCCAAGAGAAGAGCACAGAAGAGGGAGAAGUGGCUGCUCUGCGCCUCACGGCCAGAUCCCAGGCGGCGGCGGCGGCGGCGGCGCCCGGGAGCCGGAGCCUUCGCGGCGUCCACGUCCCUCCCCCGCUGCACCCCGCCCCGGCGCGAGAGGAGAGCGCGAGAACCCCAGCCGCGGCCGGGCGGGCGGCGAAGAUGGCAGAGGCACCGGCUUCCCCGGCCCCGCUUUCUCCGCUCGAAGUGGAGCUGGACCCGGAGUUCGAGCCCCAGAGCCGUCCGCGAUCCUGUACGUGGCCCCUGCAAAGGCCGGAGCUCCAAGCGAGCCCUGCCAAGCCCUCGGGGGAGACGGCCGCCGACUCCAUGAUCCCCGAGGAGGAGGACGAUGAAGACGACGAGGACGGCGGGGGACGGGCCGGCUCGGCCAUGGCGAUCGGCGGCGGCGGCGGGAGCCGCACGCUGGUCUCCGGGCUGCUCCUUGAGGACUCGGUCCGGGUGCUGGCACCCGGAGGGCAAGACCCCGGGUCUGGGCCAGCCACCGCGGCGGGCGGGCUGAGCGGGGGUACACAGGCGCUGCUGCAGCCUCAGCAACCGCUGCCACCGCCGCAGCCGGGGGCGGCUGGGGGCUCCGGGCAGCCGAGGAAAUGUUCGUCGCGGCGGAACGCCUGGGGAAACCUGUCCUACGCGGACCUGAUCACCCGCGCCAUCGAGAGCUCCCCGGACAGACGGCUCACUCUGUCCCAGAUCUACGAGUGGAUGGUGAGUUGCGUGCCCUACUUCAAGGAUAAGGGCAACAGCAACAGCUCUGCCGGCUAGAAGAACUCCAUCCGGCACAACCUGUCACUGCAUAGUCGAUUCAUGCGGGUCCAGAAUGAGGGAACUGGCAAGAGCUCUUGGUGGAUCAUCAACCCUGAUGGGGGGAAGAGCGGAAAAGCCCCCCGGCGGCGGGCUGUCUCCAUGGACAAUAGCAACAAGUAUACCAAGAGCCGUGGCCGCACAGCCAAGAAGAAGGCAGCCCUGCAGACAGCCCCCGAAUCAGCUGACGACAGUCCCUCCCAGCUCUCCAAGUGGUCUGGCAGCCCCACGUCACGCAGCAGUGAUGAGCUGGAUGCGUGGACGGACUUCCGUUCACGCACCAAUUCUAACGCCAGCACAGUCAGUGGCCGCCUGUCGCCCAUCAUGGCAAGCACAGAGUUGGAUGAAGUCCAGGACGACGAUGCGCCUCUCUCGCCCAUGCUCUACAGCAGCUCAGCGAGCCUGUCACCUUCAGUAAGCAAGCCGUGCACGGUGGAACUGCUACGGCUGACUGACAUGGCAGGCACCAUGAAUCUGAAUGAUGGGGCUGACUGAAAACCUCAUGGACGACCUGCUGGAUAACAUCACGCUCCCGCCAUCCCAGCCAUCGCCCACUGGGGGACUCAUGCAGCGGAGUUCUAGCUUCCCGUAUACCACCAAGGGCUCGGGCCUGAGCUCCCCAACCAGCUCCUUUAACAGCACGGUGUUUGGACCUUCAUCUCUGAACUCCCUACGCCAGUCUCCCAUGCAGACCAUCCAAGAGAACAAGCCAGCUACCUUCUCUUCCAUGUCACACUAUGGUAACCAGACACUCCAGGACCUGCUCACUUCGGACUCACUUAGCCACAGCGAUGUCAUGAUGACACAGUCGGACCCCUUGAUGUCUCAGGCCAGCACCGCUGUGUCUGCCCAGAAUUCCCGCCGGAACGUGAUGCUUCGCAAUGAUCCGAUGAUGUCCUUUGCUGCCCAGCCUAACCAGGGAAGUGUGGUCAAUCAGAACUUGCUCCACCACCAGCACCAAACCCAGGGCGCUCUUGGUGGCAGCCGUGCCUUGUCGAAUUCUGUCAGCAACAUGGGCUUGAGUGAGUCCAGCAGCCUUGGGUCAGCCAAACACCAGCAGCAGUCUCCUGUCAGCCAGUCUAUGCAAACCCUCUCGGACUCUCUCUCAGGCUCCUCCUUGUACUCAACUAGUGCAAACCUGCCCGUCAUGGGCCAUGAGAAGUUCCCCAGCGACUUGGACCUGGACAUGUUCAAUGGGAGCUUGGAAUGUGACAUGGAGUCCAUUAUCCGUAGUGAACUCAUGGAUGCUGAUGGGUUGGAUUUUAACUUUGAUUCCCUCAUCUCCACACAGAAUGUUGUUGGUUUGAACGUGGGGAACUUCACUGGUGCUAAGCAGGCCUCAUCUCAGAGCUGGGUGCCAGGCUGAAGGAUCACUGAGGAAGGGGAAGUGGGCAAAGCAGACCCUCAAACUGACACAAGACCUACAGAGAAAACCCUUUGCCAAAUCUGCUCUCAGCAAGUGGACAGUGAUACCGUUUACAGCUUAACACCUUUGUGAAUCCCACGCCAUUUUCCUAACCCAGCAGAGACUGUUAAUGGCCCCUUACCCUGGGUGAAGCACUUACCCUUGGAAUAGAACUCUAAAAAGUAUGCAAAAUCUUCUUUGUACAGGGUGGUGAGCCGCCUGCCAGUGGAGGACAGCACCCCUCAGCACCACCCACCCUCGUUCAGAGCACACCGUGAGCCCUCUUCGGCCAUUCUGUGGUGUUUUAAUAUUGCGAUGGUUUAUGGGAUGUUUUAAGUGUUGUUCUUGUGUUUGUUUUCCUUUGACUUUCUGAGUUUUUCACAUGCAUUAACUUGCGGUAUUUUUCUGUUAAAAUGUUAACCGUCCUUCCCCUAGCAAAUUUAAAAACAGAAAGACAAUGUUGUACCAGUUACCAUUCCAGGUUUGAGCAUCACAAGCUUUUGAGCGCAUGGAACUCCAUAAACUAACAAAUUACAUAAACUAAAGGGGGAUUUUCUUUCUUCUUUUGUUUGGUAGAAAAUUAUCCUUUUCUAAAAACUGAACAAUGGCACAAUUGUUUGCUAUGCGCACCCGUCCAGGACUGAACCAUGCAUAGGCAAAACGAGUGGAGCACAGCGUCCAGCCCAGUGUGUUUCCAGUUCUGAGUCAGGGUGAUCUGUGGACGGGACCCCAGCACCAGGUCUACGGGUGCCAGAUCAGUAGGGCCUGUGAUCUCCUGUCAGUGUCCUCAGCUAAUGUGAACAGUGUUGGUCUGCUGGUUAGAAACUAGAAUAAUGAUAUUUUCAGGAAAGAAAUCAGCUCAGCUCUCCACUCAUUGCCAAAUGUCACCCAAAAAGGGUUUAGUUUUAAGGAGAAAGAAAAGGAAAAAAAAAAAAAGUCCUGUUUUGCUUUGCAGAACAAAUGAACUUACAGGUGAGCAUUAAGCUUGCAGUGAGAAAUGUGCAAAGAGUAAAAACCCAAGUCAAUGCUGAGGCAGUUCCAACUUCACUGUUUUCCUAAAUACACAUCCUUGAUUAUUUUCAGCCUUGCUAUAUAAUCUGAUCUGCUAGAAGUGUAUGAGUGAGAGGCAAUAGCAUAUAAACUGAUUUUUUAAAUAUAAGCUUAGGUUGUAAUUGUACAAGCGACUCAAUGGAAGUACAAAAUAGGGCAGUUUUAACUUUUUUUUCUGCUUCUGUGGAUUUCAUUUUGUUGUGUUUUCAAAAAGUUAUGGUGCUGUAUAGGUGCUUUCUGUUUAACCUGGAAAGUGUGAUUAUAUUCGUUACCUUCUUUGGUAGACGGAAUAGUUGGGACCACCUUUGGUACAUAUGAAAUUGGUAUAACGAUGCUCUGAUUAGCACAGCAUAUGCAUACUUCUCCAAAGUGAUAUAUGAAGACUCUUUUCUUUGCAUAAAAAGCAUUAGGCGUAUAAAUGUAUAAAUAUAUUUUAUUAUGUACAGUACAAAAAUGGAACCUUAUGCAUGGGCCUUAGGAAUACAGGCUAGUAUUUCAGCACAGACUUCCCUGCUUGAGUUCUUGCUGAUGCUUGCACCGUGACAGUGGGCACCAACACAGACGUGCCACCCAACCCCCUGCACACACCACCGGCCACCAGGGGCCCCCUUGUGCGCCUUGGCUUUAUAACUCCUCUGGGGGUGAUAUUGGUGGUGAUCACAGCUCCUAGCAUAAUGAGAGUUCCAUUUGGUAUUGUCACACGUCUCCUGCCUCGCUUGGGUUGCCAUGUUUGAGCGAUGGCCCUGUUGAUUUCACCCUGCCUUUUACUGAAUCUGUAAAUUGUUGUGCAAUUGUGGUUAUAGUAGACUGUAGCACAUUGCCUUUUCUAAACUGCUACAUGUUUAUAAUCUUCAUUUUUAAAGUAUGUAUAAUUUUUUAAAGUAUGUAUUCUAUUCAUAUGGUCUGCUUGUCAGUGAGCCAGACUUGCUUACUAUAUUCCUUUAUAAUAAUGCUAGCCACUUCCUGGAUUCUUUAGUAAUGUGCUGUAUGCAAGAACUUUCCAGUAGCAGUGAAGGAGGGUUGCCUCUCCAAGCUUCCUAAGGGAUGCUGCCCUGGGUGGGGAUGCAUUGCAGAGGCAGUAGUAGCAUGGGGGCUAGAGUGGGGAGCGAGAUGGAAAAGGGUGGGGGGAUAGGAGAAUUCUAGAGUGCUUCCAGCAUGAGGGUCCUGAGAACUUCUGUCCUGAGUUCAGAGAAACAUGCAAAGUAACUAACAAAAUCGCUACUUGCCUUUGCAGUUUUACAGACCCAGGGAGCUGCUUUGGGAGUGAGAAAGGCAACCCUCCAAUGUGUUUCAACUUUAAAAUGUUGAAUUCUUUUCAGACAUGUGGUAUCUCAUUUAUUCUCCUUUUCUAGCGUUUGUUGAAUUUCAGGCAGAAUGUCUUACAGAAUGUCCUAGAACCAGAUUAUCAUUUAAUCCGAAACAGCUGAGGAAGGGACAGAGAAGGUACAAGGGCAAGGCAGCAUAAAACAGAUCAGGAGAAUGAAGAGGGAAUGCUUUGGUUUUUUGUUCUGUUUUGUUUUUUCUUUUUCAAGUAACUAAAACAGCAUCUACAUGUAGAGUGUCGUGGAGAGCUGAGACCAGGGUAAAGUCAAGUGCAGCAUCAGUACUGCGAGACCCACCAGCCCCUGGAGAGGGUCAGCUGAGAAUCUGGUAGUGAAGCCUGUGUAGGGUCCCGGCACCCUCACCCUCAGCCACCUGCAGAGAGGCCAGGGCCCCAGAGACUAGCCCGGUUCUGAAGUGGGCAGGGGUGCUGCCAGAGCCUUCCGCCCCUUAUAUUGAGACCCUGCUUUCAGGACAGGCCAGCCGUUGGCCACCAUGUCACAUUCUGAGUGAGUGUCACGGGUCCCUAACAAUAAUUUUCUGAUCUGGAGCAUAUCAGCAGAAUGCUUAGCCUCAAGGGGCCUGGCAGCUGUAAUGUUUGAUUUAUGAUGAGAACUAUCCGAGGCCACACUUGGCCUCUAAAUAAGCUGCUCUAGGGAGCCGCCUACUUUUUGGUGAGAAAUUAGAAGAGUACCUAAUGUUGAAAACAUGACAUGCGCUCUUGGGAUCUGCUGUUCUCUCCAGGGCUCCAGAACCUGAUACCUGUUACCAAAGCUAGGAAAGAGCUUUAUCACAAGCCUUCACUGUCCUGGCAUGAGAACUGGCUGCCAGGCUCAGUGUACCCCAUUAAAUGUGAAUGAAUCUGA